AUCGUUAGCUUCUCCUGAUAAACUAAUUGCCUCACAUUGUCACUGCAAAUCGACACCUAUUAAUGGGUCUCACCUCCCAACUGCUUCCCCCUCUGUUCUUCCUGCUAGCAUGUGCCGGCAACUUUGUCCACGGACACAAGUGCGAUAUCACCUUACAGGAGAUCAUCAAAACUUUGAACAGCCUCACAGAGCAGAAGACUCUGUGCACCGAGUUGACCGUAACAGACAUCUUUGCUGCCUCCAAGCAGCAUGCAUGUCUGCCCACCUCCAGACACACAGGCACCAUCUGCCGCCCCCCAUCAGCCCGUGUCCCUUCCACCUCGACUCGCCUACAAAGCCCAGAGAGAACACAACUGAGAAGGAAACCUUCUGCAGGGCUGCGACUGUGCUCCGGCAGUUCUACAGCCACCAUGAGAAGGACACUCGCUGCCUGGGUGCGACUGCACAGCAGUUCCACAGGCACAAGCAGCUGAUCCGAUUCCUGAAACGGCUCGACAGGAACCUCUGGGGCCUGGCGGGCUUGAAUUCCUGUCCUGUGAAGGAAGCCAACCAGAGUACGUUGGAAAACUUCUUGGAAAGGCUAAAGACGAUCAUGAGAGAGAAAUAUUCAAAGUGUUCGAGCUGAAUAUUUUAAUUUAUGAGUUUUUGAUAGCUUUAUUUUUUAAGUAUUUAUAUAUUUAUAACUCAUCAUAAAAUAAAGUAUAUAUAGAAUCUAA